AUACUAGCCCACCAGACUCAGAGACGGAACCAGAGACGGGCCAGAGCAUCCCCCUCCUCCACCAUGAAACUCGCUGUCACCCUCACCCUGGUCACACUGGCUCUCUGCUGCAGCUCCGCUUCUGCAGAGAUCUGCCCGAGCUUUCAGCGUGUCAUCGAAACCCUCCUCAUGGACACACCCUCCAGUUAUGAGGCUGCCAUGGAACUUUUCAGCCCUGAUCAAGACAUGAGGGAGGCAGGGGCUCAGCUGAAGAAGCUGGUGGACACCCUCCCCCAAAAGCCCAGAGAAAGCAUCAUUAAGCUCAUGGAAAAAAUAGCCCAAAGCUCACUGUGUAAUUAGCAUUUAGAAGCUGAAGAUCCCCAACUGCUCCAGCCUCUGCCGCUGCCAUGCUUUGAGUCCACGCCCACCAGCCUUGCUCUCUUCAAUAAACCACAAGCAUCUCA